GCUCCCGUAAGCCCCAAGGCGACCUCCAGCUGUCAGCGCUGAGCACAGCGCCCAGGGAGAGGGACAGACAGCCGGCUGCAUGGGACAGCGGAACCCAGAGUGAGAGGGGAGGUGGCAGGACAGACAGACAGCAGGGGCGGACGCAGAGACAGACAGCGGGGACAGGGAGGCCGACACGGACAUCGACAGCCCAUAGAUUCCUAACCCAGGGAGCCCCGGCCCCUCUCGCCGCUUCCCACCCCAGACGGAGCGGGGACAGGCUGCCGAGCAUCCUCCCACCCGCCCUCCCCGUCCUGCCUCCUCGGCCCCUGCCAGCUUCCCCCGCUUGAGCACGCAGGGCGUCCGAGGACGCGCUGGGCCUCCGCACCCGCCCUCAUGGAGGCCGUGGAGACCGGGGAACGGCCCACCUUCGGAGCCUGGGACUACGGGGUCUUUGCCCUCAUGCUCCUGGUGUCCACUGGCAUCGGGCUGUGGGUCGGGCUGGCUCGGGGCGGGCAGCGCAGCGCUGAGGACUUCUUCACCGGGGGCCGGCGCCUGGCGGCCCUGCCCGUGGGCCUGUCGCUGUCUGCCAGCUUCAUGUCGGCCGUGCAGGUGCUGGGCGUGCCGUCGGAGGCCUAUCGCUAUGGCCUCAAGUUCCUCUGGAUGUGCCUGGGCCAGCUUCUGAACUCGGUCCUCACCGCCCUGCUCUUCAUGCCCGUCUUCUACCGCCUGGGCCUCACCAGCACCUACGAGUACCUGGAGAUGCGCUUCAGCCGCGCAGUGCGGCUCUGCGGGACUUUGCAGUACAUUGUAGCCACGAUGCUGUACACCGGCAUCGUAAUCUACGCACCGGCCCUCAUCCUGAACCAAGUGACCGGGCUGGACAUCUGGGCGUCGCUCCUGUCCACCGGAAUUAUCUGCACCUUCUACACGGCUGUGGGCGGCAUGAAGGCUGUGGUCUGGACUGAUGUGUUCCAGGUCGUGGUGAUGCUAAGUGGCUUCUGGGUUGUCCUGGCACGCGGUGUCAUGCUUGUGGGCGGGCCCCGCCAGGUGCUCACGCUGGCCCAGAACCACUCCCGGAUCAACCUCAUGGACUUUAACCCUGACCCGAGGAGCCGCUAUACAUUCUGGACUUUUGUGGUGGGUGGCACGUUGGUGUGGCUCUCCAUGUAUGGCGUGAACCAGGCGCAGGUGCAGCGCUACGUGGCUUGCCGCACAGAGAAGCAGGCCAAGCUGGCCCUGCUCAUCAACCAGGUCGGCCUGUUCCUGAUCGUGUCCAGCGCUGCCUGCUGUGGCAUCGUCAUGUUUGUGUUCUACACUGACUGCGACCCUCUCCUCCUGGGGCGCAUCUCUGCCCCAGACCAGCUGUCUGGGAGGCUGACCCCCAGUUCUCCCCAGUACAUGCCUCUGCUGGUGCUGGACAUCUUCGAAGAUCUGCCUGGAGUCCCCGGGCUUUUCCUGGCCUGUGCUUACAGUGGCACCCUCAGCACAGCAUCCACCAGCAUCAAUGCUAUGGCUGCAGUCACUGUAGAAGACCUCAUCAAACCUCGGCUGCGGAGCCUGGCACCCAGGAAACUCGUGAUUAUCUCCAAGGGGCUCUCACUCAUCUACGGAUCGGCCUGUCUCACCGUGGCAGCCCUGUCCUCACUGCUCGGAGGAGGUGUCCUUCAGGGCUCCUUCACCGUCAUGGGAGUCAUCAGCGGCCCCCUGCUGGGAGCCUUCAUCUUGGGAAUGUUCCUGCCGGCCUGCAACACACCGGGCGUCCUCGCGGGACUAGGCGCGGGCUUGGCGCUGUCGCUGUGGGUGGCCUUGGGCGCCACGCUGUACCCACCCAGCGAGCAGACCAUGAGGGUCCUGCCAUCGUCGGCUGCCCGCUGCGUGGCUCUCUCAGUCAACGCCUCUGGCCUCCUGGACCCGGCUCUCCUCCCUGCUAACGACUCCAGCAGGGCCCCCAGCUCAGGAAUGGACGCCAGCCGACCCGCCUUAGCUGACAGCUUCUAUGCCAUCUCCUAUCUCUAUUACGGUGCCCUGGGCACGCUGACCACUGUGCUGUGCGGAGCCCUCAUCAGCUGCCUGACAGGCCCCACCAAGCGCAGCACCCUGGCCCCGGGAUUGUUGUGGUGGGACCUCGCACGGCAGACAGCAUCAGUGGCCCCCAAGGAAGAAGUGGCCAUCCUGGAUGACAACUUGGUCAAGGGUCCUGAAGAACUCCCCACUGGAAACAAGAAGCCCCCUGGCUUCCUGCCCACCAAUGAGGAUCGUCUGUUUUUCUUGGGGCAGAAGGAGCUGGAGGGGGCUGGCUCUUGGACCCCCUGUGUUGGACAUGAUGGUGGUCGAGACCAGCAGGAGACAAACCUCUGAGGACAGGGCCAGCCGCGGGACUGACACCCUGGGAUGGAACCUCAGGAUGGGCCAAACCCAGACAACGGGCCCAUGGCCUUGGGCUCUGAUUGGCUGGAUUGCCUUGUAUGCAAAUGAGUUCAGGACUACAAUACCCUACCCUAUGGGGAGGCCCUGCCUCCGGGAGGUCAUUUUUUAAAUCCAGCCCCUUGCUUCAACCGUCCCCAGUAUUAGACGCUGCAGCCCUGACGGCUCCCCCCAAAUAAGGCUGGGUUUUUCUCUCUCUCUUUUUUUUUUUUUUUUUUUUUUGAGACAGGGUCAUGCUCUGUCACCCAGGCUGGAGUGCAGUGGUGUGAUCUCGGCUCACUGCAACCUCUGCCUCCCAGGCUCAAGUGAUUCUCCUGCCUCAGCCUCUUGAGUAGCUGGGAUUGUAGGUGCCCACCACCAUGCCCAGCCAACUUUUUGUAUUUUUAGUAGAGACAGGGUUUCACCAUGUUGGUCAGGCUGGUCUCGAACUCCUGACCUCAAGUGAUCCACCUGCCUCGGCCUCCCAAAGUGCUGGGUUACAGGCGUAAGCUACCAUGCCCAGCCUACCGUUUUUCUCAAUCUAUAAUAGAAAGCCACCACGCCCAGGUAAUUUUUGUAAUUUUGUAUUUUUGUAGAGACGGGGUUUUGCCAUGUUGGCCAGGCUGGUCUCAAACUCCUGAUCUCAGGUGAUCCUCCUGCCUUGGCCUCCCAAAGGGCUGGGAUUACAGGGGUGAGCCACCGCGCCCCACCUCUUUCUUAUUUUCUUCCUGGGAUUGGGGAGGGGAUGAUUCAGACCCCACAUGGCCUCCAACCUUGGCCCACACACCUGCCAUGGCUCCCAUCAUCCUGAGCAUGCUAGCGUCCCCUCCUCACCUGACAAUGGAGGCUCUCGAAUUGGGUUGUGUCCCCCCAAAAUUUAUGUCUACCCAGAACCUCAGAACAUGAGCUUACUUGGAAAUAGGGUCUUUGCAGGUGUAACUGGUUAAAUUAAAAGAGGUAUUACUGGAGGAGGAUGGAUGAAUCCAGUGACUGGUUCCUCAUAUGAAGUAGAGAAGAGAUGCAGAGAAACACAUGGGGAAGAUGCCACGUGAAGACAGAGGCAGUGGUUGGAUCAAUGCAUCUACGAGUCGGAGAACCCAAGGAUUGCCAGCAACAACCAGAAAUCAGGAGGGGGGCAUGAGAUGCAUUAUUUCUUAGAGCCUUUAGAGGGAACAUGGCCCUACUGACACCUUGAUGUCAGACUUCUGGCUGCUAGAACUGUCAGAGAAUAAAUUUCUGUUGUUUGAUGCCA